ACUUUUCAGGGGACAUUCAGAGGCAUCAGCCCCUUCCUCCUCACCAGCUCCCAGAGUUCCCAUCUCCAUCCCCAAUCCUAAAGAAGGAAAUCGAUGCCACGGUCCUCAAGGAGCCCUGGGGACCCAGGCGCCCUACUCGAAGAUGUGGCCCACAAUCCCAGACCCCGGAGGAUUGCCCAGCGAGGCCGGAACACCAGCAGGAUGGCAGAGGACACCUCCCCAAACAUGAAUGACAACAUCCUGUUGCCUGUCCGCAACAAUGACCAAGCCCUAGGCCUGACUCAGUGCAUGCUGGGAUGUGUGUUCUGGCUGCUGGUUUCACCCAUCCAUCCACCUGUUGAGUUCAUCAGUUCUCCCAGACCUUAUUUCAUAGCCUGGUUCACCUGUUUUGCCUGCUCCCUGAGAACUCAGGCCCAGCAGGUUCUGUUUAACACGUGCAGAUGCAAGCUGCUGUGCCAGAAGCUCAUGGAGAAGACAGGCAUUCUGCUCCUCUGUGCUUUCGGAUUCUGGAUGUUUUCUAUUCACUUACCAUCGAAAAUGAAAGUCUGGCAGGAUGACAGCAUAAAUGGUCCACUGCAGAGCUUGAGGUUGUACCAGGAGAAGGUGCGACAUCACAGUGGGGAAAUCCAGGACCUCCGAGGUAGCAUGAACCAGCUCAUUGCCAAGCUCCAGGAGAUGGAAGCCAUGUCCGAUGAGCAAAAAAUGGCCCAGAAAAUAAUGAAGAUGAUACACGGAGAUUACAUCGAAAAGCCAGACUUUGCCCUGAAGUCUAUAGGGGCCAGCAUUGACUUUGAGCACACGUCAGUCACCUAUAACCAUGAGAAGGCCCACUCCUACUGGAACUGGAUCCAGCUGUGGAACUACGCACAGCCCCCAGACGUGAUCCUUGAGCCCAACGUGACACCUGGCAAUUGCUGGGCCUUUGAGGGUGACCGCGGCCAGGUGACCAUCCAAUUGGCUCAGAAGGUUUACCUGUCCAACCUCACGCUGCAGCACAUCCCCAAGACCAUCUCAUUGUCAGGCAGCCUGGACACCGCCCCCAAGGACUUCGUCAUCUAUGGCAUGGAGGGCUCCCCCAAGGAGGAGGUGUUCCUGGGGGCAUUUCAGUUUCAGCCAGAAAACAUCAUCCAGAUGUUCCCACUCCAGAACCAGCCGGCCCGGGCUUUCAGUGCGGUCAAGGUGAAGAUCUCAAGCAACUGGGGGAACCCAGGCUUCACUUGCCUGUACCGCGUGCGAGUGCAUGGCUCUGUGGCCCCGCCCAGAGAGCAGCCUCACCAGAACCCCUACCCUAAGAGAGAUUAAAAUUUAUUCUUUACCCCCA